CCUCGUGAUCCGCCUGCCUCAGCCUCCCAAAGUGCUGGGAUUACAGGCAUGAUUUCUUUUUUUUUUUAAUCAGUAACAUGGAAGCAGGAGGCAGGUAGGUUUAAUAUGCUACUGCCUUUCCACCCAGCUUUGCUUUUCUCCUUUUUUCCUCUUCUUCCUCUUUAUUUCCAUCUCUCUUUCCCAAUAUAAUUCUUCUUCCUCUUCCCCUCCUCUUCCUCCUCCUUCACUUCCUUGUUCUUCCUCCCUCCUCUUCCUCCUCUUCCUCCCCCUCCUCCUCUUCCUUUUUCUCCUCUUUCUUCUUCCCUCCUCCCCCUCCCCCUCUUCCUCCUUCUUCUCAUCCUCCUCUUCCUCCUCAGGGCCAAUCCUACUCUACAUCAUUGCAUUGUACAUUGAUAGGCACCUAAAAUUCAACUGAAUUGCACCAACUCUGAAUUACUACUUCUGAGGGCUUCUCCAGUAGCACCCCUGCCCACUUUAUCAACAAGAAUUUGUGUUUAAAAGGCAGAAGUCACCAUCCUGUGACCCACCAAAGGUCGGCAACAAGAGGGCUCUCUCUUGACUCUGGUUCUGGGUGACACCACUCGUGGGGUGCGGGGGAGUCUGCCAAUAUUCUAUUCCUACUCCUGCCCCUCUUAGUAACAAAGCCCUUUGUGUUAGUCAACUUGGGCUGCCAGACAAAAUACCAUAGACUGAGAGGCUUAAACAACAGAAAUUUAUUCUCACAGUUCUGGAGGCCAGAAGUCCAAGAUCAAGGUGCUGGCUGAUUCUGUUUCUGGUGAGGGCUCUCUUCCUGGUUUUUAGAUGGCUGCCUUCUUACAUGGCCUGUCUUCUAUGCAUUGGUUGGGGGUGGGAGGUUGGUGGUGUCUCUUCCUUUUCUUAGAAGGCCACAAAUCCUCCCAGAUUAGGUUCUACCUUUAUGACUUCAUUUAACUUUACCUUCCUAACAGCCCUAUUUCCAAAUACAGUUACAUUGGGGUGUAGAGCUUCAAAUGAAUUUUUUGGGGGACACACUUCAGUCCAUAGCAGCCUUGAGUUUAUCUGAGGUGGCAGUGUACCCAACUAAACAUGACAUUUCCCAGCCUCUCUUACAGCUAUAUGUGGCCAAGUGACUCAACUCUACACAAUGAGGUGCAGGCUGAGGAGCGGUGUGGUAUCCAGGAAGACCUAUUCAAAGGGAGAGGGUCCCUUUUACCUCUUGUUCCUCUUCCUGUGGUUUGGAAUGAGCUGAUGGUGCCUGAGCUCAAGCAGCCAUCUCGGACUCAGAGAUGACGUAAGGAUGAAAGCUUCCUGGGUUGGCAGAACUGAAGACAGAAGGACCCUAGGUUCUUGGUGACCGAGGGCUCCCCCAAGCCUGGACUGCCCACCUCUAGUCUGGGAGAAUAUCUAUCUUCCAUAAGCCACUAUUUAGGAGUCUUUGUUAUUGUCAGCAAAUGCUAUUUCCAGCUGAUGCAUGGAAGCUCCCCUGGCCCUGAGUUUUGAGCUUCAGGCAAAGACAUUCAAAGUUCCUCUAAGGCCACUGCUACUUUUUCUCCUACCCUCCCUUCUUUGGAAGCAUAAUUUUAUCCAAGAGUUCCCGAUUCAUGCACAUUUGUCCUCCUUCUGUCUUUUGUUUUUUUUUCUUUCCUCUGCUUUCUCCUCUCUCCCUCCCUCUCUUCUUUCCUUCCUUUUCCUUCCCUCCUUCUAAUAUUUAUUGAGCACCUACUAUGUUCCAGGUACCGUGCUAGCUGCCAUGAUUAGAAGUAGGUAUAGGAGAUAAUCCCUUCUCCCCAGUAACCCAGAAUCCAGGCUUUCUGGACAACAUAAAGAGAAUAUGAUGGCAGGAUAGAUCAAAGGAAAGGACAUUAAAUCCGAUAAAAAGGGCCUGGGGCGUUCCAGAAGGAGGUCACACUUGGCCUGAGAUCUAAAGUAGAACUUUUGUGUUGCUGGUAAUGAGGAAAAGAGGGUGGAGGACAAAAUCCCAGGCACAGGGACCAGCACAGUGUUACUUUAUUCGGCUUCAUCACCUGUAAAAUGGGGACAGUAAUAGUAACAUGAAUAAGUGAAUGGAUGGACUAGUAAGUGUGCAGUUCAUGCUACUUUUUAAUAUUAUUCUUGUUGGCAAUGUGCUGUUCACCCUGGUAGGCACAGCCCUGUAUCAGUUUUGGAGACAAGCUUCACAGAGGACAUGUGACUUACUUGUCCAUGGUCACACAACUAUAAAAAGGCACUGCUCAAACCCAAGUGUCCUGGUCCCUGGUACAGUGACCUUUAUAUCUUUACCCUCUGCCUUUGCAUUAAGUGCUGAGGGAAUGCAAAGUGAGGGAAAGAUCGGUGUGUGGUGGGGGGAAAAUCUAGAGGGCUUCCUGGAAGAGGAGAUUUUUGAGAGCAUUUUGGUAGAAAGGGAAAAAGGAAGGCAUUCCAGGGAAGGAGUGUAUGAUGGGUGCCAUCCAUCAGGGUGUUGGAGGAUGGGCUGGGGGGCUAGCUGGCUGGCAGAGGAUUUGAACUCUGAAGAUUGGUGAGACACGAGGUAGAGCAGGCAAACAGGCAAAAUCAGAGGAUGAACCAUGAUUACAGGCACCCUGAUGGCCAGAUUGUGGAGUGAAGCUCUAAGCCAGUGGGCCACAGGGAGCCACAGGAAGUUCUUGAGCAAGAAGGCUGGUCAAAAUGAAAUGAGACUUUGGGGAGAAAGGAAAGAAAGAAACAAACUUGUCUUUACUAAGAACCAGUAUGAACUAGGCAGUAGGUUGGCCAUUUUCAAAUUUAUUACUUAAUUUGAGCCUCACUACAGCCCCAUUAGGUUGGUAUCAAUGUCCCCAUUUCAUAGAUGAGAAAACUGAGGUCAAGAGAGACUCAGCCUUAGAUAUGAGUCAGUGGUGGAGCUAAAAGAUAGGUUAGACUGAACCUAAAUCUGUGCUUUUUCCACUGCACCAUGUGGCUUUAUGCUGGUCUCACUCUAGGAAUAUUUCUUGUACUGUGAGUGUCCCAACUAAGGCAUUUCCUAGCCAGGGCUAGAGUCUUUUAAUAGCCCAGAUACCCCCUGGGCUCACUCUGGGUCACACUGGGCAUAGAGGCCUUAGUACCUUCGGGAGUUUUGGGGACUCCCAGCAUGGGGUAGGAUUAAGUGCUUGGCUUCCAGGUCUGAAAGAAGUAGGUUCAAAUCCCAGCUAUACUGUGCAUGAACUGGAGAGUAAUAUGCUUUAGUUCACAGAGCCUCAACCCAGGUGGGGCAGCGGGAUGAGCCCUGGAUUGGGAGCCAACCCAAGCAUAGGUUGAAACCCUAGCUGGAAGUGACAGGCACUGAGGAGGUGAAAUGGUGUCUUUAUUAUUUCAAAAUAAUGAGUUGGAGGGGGUAGCGAGGAAAUAAGGUUGCCCAUGAGGUGAUCAUUGUUGAGGCUGGGUGAUGGGUUUAUGGGGGUUCAUUACACUAUUCAUUCUACUGCUCUGUUUGAAAAAUCUCCAUUAAUAAAUAGGCUGGGCAUAGUGGCUCACGCCUGUAAUCCCAGCACUUUAAGAGGCUAAGGUGGGAGUCACUUGAGGUCAGGAGUUUGAGACCAGCCUGGCCAACAUGGUGAAACCCUGUCUUUACUAAAACUACAAAAAAUUUAGCUGGGCAUGGUGGUGCACGUCUGUAAUUUUAGCUACUCAGGAGACUGAGGUGGGAGAAUCACUUGAACCCGGGAGGCAGAGGUUGCAAUGAGCUGAGAUCAAGCCACAGCACUCCAGCCUGGGUGACAGAGCGAGACUCUGUCUCAAAAAAAAUAAAAUAAAACAAAAAGAAAAAAGAAAAAAGAAAAUCCCCAUUAAAAAAUAAAAUAAUAACAAUAACACCAAAAACCUUUUUGAAAACCCAGCUACGUUCACCACACCCUCCUCUAGCUGGAACAGCAUCUCUGGCUCCCAGGCACUGUUCUGCUUUAAAACUUCAUCAGGCAAGAGCAGCCAAGGUGAGAAUCCCUGCUUAUAGCCAUCUCUCACUAGCUGUGUACCUCAAGCCACUGUCUUUCCGCUGCUGAGCCUCAGUCUCCUCAUCUGAAAAACGAGGUGAAGAUUCUUUUAAGUUCAGGGGUACAAGUGCAGGUUUGUUACAUGGGUAAACUUGUGUCAUGGAGGUGUGUUGUACAGAUUAUUUCAUCAUCCAGGUAUUAAGUCUAGUAAUGGGGUGAAGAUUCUAAUGACCUCAUGGAACUGUUGUGAAGUGUAAGUGGGAUGAUACAGGAUCCCAUGGGCUGGGCAUAGCCCGUGACAGAUGUGAGCAGGUCAGCCUGGGUUUUCCAGUCACUCUAAGCACCACCAGGCUGCUAGCCACAUUCGGUGAGGAACCCUAAGCCAAUACGUGCAGCAGAGGCCAGCCGAUGACCUGACAGGGGAUAAGUCCCACCUUCUGGGCAACUUUUACGAGUCUUCUGUGUAAGUACUGUGUGCUAACCGAUUGCGCUGCUGGAGCUGCAGCCUUAUGAGUUUUCUAAAUCACAAGAAGUUCAUCACCUAGUGGGGCUUUUUUAUCUGCCUUUCCUCACUGCUUAAAGACCAAGCCCACAUCUUUCCUUCUCCUGUCUGCUGUCGGAGCAUAAGUGUGUGCCACACGUGACCAGGUGUGGCAGAGUCAGAGCAGGGGGUGGCUUCUGUGGAAGUAGGAGUGAAAGUGUGGAAACAAGUGAGUGCGUGUGUUGACAGGCAUCUGCAUUUGUGUUAGUUGUGCUUACUCAGAGGUCCACAGGCUUGUGGCAGAUUUCAGAAGCUGGUCCUUCUUCAGCAGCUCUCUCGGAGGCACACCUCCCUGAUCUGCAUCUAUGCGGAGUUACCCAGCACAAGGACACCAGGGUCGCUGUGUCACCACCAGAGGCACAGGUAGGGGGAUAAGAUUGGAUGGUGGGGGAAAGGCCUGGGCCUUAUCCGCCAGCCCUGCCACUGGCCUCCAGGACUUAGCCUCGGUUUCUCAAACUGUGUCAGGGACGAGUAAAUGGGAUGAGCAGCCCUUGGCAAGGAGUGGGCGCUAGGAAAUCAUCAGUGAAGGAGGGAGUGAAUGAAUGCAGGCCUGUGUGGCGACUGCUUCAGCAUGGCAGACAAGGUGACGUAUCAGAGCCUUGAGGGUGGGAGCUCCCCAGGUUGGGAAGGGACAGACACGUGGGCCAAUCCUCUGGACAGGAAUAGAGAACGAGGAGGAAACAAGCGCAGAAGCUGGAGCGGGUGGAGAAGAGCAGGGGAGACGGUUCGCAGCAGGAGAAAAGAAGCGAGGAGUCACAGGGAGGGGCCUCCUGGACACCGCUCCCAAAGCCACGCGAAAGUGGAAGCGCGGGGCCUCGGGAUGCCCAUCCAGCCGGCUGCCCGCGCGCUGGCCGGGGUUCCAGGACUCCUUCCUGCUCCGCCGGGCUCUGCAGCGCCGCCUGGUGGACACGCGGCGCUCCGCCCGGGCUCCAGCCGCCAGCCGGCGCGCCGGGGAUCCCGCGGCUGUUCGGGAAAAAGCUGGAGAGAGUCGGGGGGCGCGCCUUGGGGAGGGGCAUUUGUCCCUCCGAGGAGGCUCGCACCUCGGCCUGGACACGCAGCAGAUACUGGCACCCACCCUUCACUUACCGCGCGCCCGGGGUGACUCGGAUCCGUCCAACACGUCGGGGAAUCCUUUCUGUCCUCACCCCCGGGCGCCCCAGCGCCGGAACGCUGCUGCCUCUGUGUAGCUGCUCCCGGAAGGAGUUUCAUCAAACUUUUAAGGGGCUUUGGUUUUGGGUUGUGUUGAUAAAAUACCAAGAAGGGGCAUGAAGGCACGAACGUCCCGGGUUCGUCUCCCUGCUGGUCCCAAGCCUGAAUCCCAGGGCGGGGGAAUGUCUAGGUCCUUCCGGGCCGGCAAGGUGUGGUCGCUCAGGGACCCCUGUCCGAAGACGCUAGGGAAAAGAGGCACAGCCUGUGGGUCGCAGUGGCCAGGAGCGCGUGGCCGCUGCUGGUGAGAGAGUGGUAGACGCCUGGCUUUCAGGUCCUGAGCUGCGGGCACCGGAGCGUGGGACCCCGGCUGCAGCACCGCCACGCGCUCCCGCCCUCCCACCUGCAGGGCGGGGGAUGUCUGUCCAAGAGGCCGGGGCGACAAGCCCGCCGGCCAGGAUUCUCAAGGAACCAGGCCCAGCUCAGCCUCUCUCGGCGGGACCAGAGUGGGACCGGGGCCGCGGCGUCCGAAGACGCUGCGGGCCAGGGGUCCUCCUCGGCGCCAGCUCCGUUUCCUGGGGUCUCGCGACGUCCGGACAUCAGGGUCGGGGGUGUGGAGACGGCGGCGGAGCCAGAGUCCCCACCAAGUCAGUUCCAGGAGGCGGCCCGCGCGCUUCCCGCAGUGUCCGGGAGGUCGCUGGGGGUGGCUUUGCGUGCAACCCGGGUAAAGGCCCUGCAGCCGUGAGGCUGGCGCUGGGAGGAGGGUGGAAAAUCUCAAAGUCACCAAUCCCGGUGCAAAUGGCGGCAGGGGCCGCGGGCUGUCGGACGCAGGCGAGAGGCCAAAGGCUGACUUCGCGCGGCCGUGAGUCCCCAGAGGCAACAGGGGUACCUGAGCGCCGAGGGGAUCCCGAGACUCGGAGAAACCGGAAGAGCCUGACCCCAGGGAGCGGAGAGUUUGGGGUGCGCUCUCAGAGCUGUGACUCCACGGUCCCGGAAUCCUUGGAAAGGGCGCUCUGGGCUCAGAGCUCCCAACUAGCCGGAGGACCUGGGCUAGCGCCCAGGCCUGGAGCGUCUGGGAGGGGGCGCUGGGUCUCGGCCCCCCUCCCCCCAAAAGGGACUGAGACUUUUUUCUGCGUGCUUCCUUCGGCGCUUCGGGCAGCUCUGUCCUGCGGCCCAAGCUGGGGAGAAGACAGCGGCCCGCGCCACAGGGAGCUGCGCCCGGACCCAGACUCCCGCCGCGCUUCUGCAGAGCGGAGCCCUAGGUGCCCACCUGGUAGCCCCAGAAAGGCCGGACCUGGGCGCCGGGACGCUCGCGGGGCCGCACUUGGAGGGGCUUUCCGGGUCCUGGCCGGGCGGGCUCUCCUGCGGCGCGGAAUGGAAUAGAGCGCCGGCUGCAGAGCCACCCGGACGGGGAAAAGCAGCGGUGGCGCCGGCCAGCCCCGGGUCCCGACUCUGGAGGGAGGAAGGAGCGGGCGGGUGGGGGUGGGGGUGAGGGCGAGGGUUGCGGGGAGCGUUUAGAAGGCCCUGGGCAGCCAGAAGAAGAAAAGAGGACGCACUCUCCCCUAGGGACCAGAGGGUCCCUGCGUACUCCCCCCAGGCCCGGGACACAGGUUCCCCCAGCGCCCCUCCGCCUCCCAGUCUAUUCGGCUUGCCCCAGCGCGCUGCCCCACGUCCCCGAGGCCCCGGCCCAGGCCCAGCCGGCGAGUCCCGGCCUGCUCCACUCUGCACAAAACGAAACCCAAAUGCCCAAAAAGCUCAGGAGGGAAAUUUAACAAAAACCCUGUCCCCCGCCCCACACCCCCUUUCACUUUUAACAAGCCAGCUGCCAAGAGAAAAUUGAAAUAAAAACGAAAUGAUAGAUAGCGGAGGACACUAUUUUCCAAAUGGUGAAAUAUCCUCUAAAAAUAUGUUCCCCAAGGCCAACUUCGCGGCUGGUAGCCCCUUCCGACGCCUUUGCCUCCCAGAAAAUCACAACAAAGCGAUCGGAAAUUCAGCCACGGUCCCGGGAAGAAGGAGUAGCAGUGAGGCCCCGGAACCCACUGCGGCCGAAACUGCCAUGCUCUCUUUAACCAAAAUAAAAAAGAUAAGAAGAAGAAGUAAAACCCUUUAAUACAUCAAAUAUACGGAAUUUUAAUCUUUAAAGCGAUACAUUGUCUAUUAUUUUAGUACAUGACGUAAACCUUGUCCCCUUCUCAGCGGGUGGACUUAAAAAUUAAAAAUAGUUAAGUGUUCCUUUUAAAGAACAAAAUAAGGCAAAUGAGGUUUUGGAAUAGAAUUUUUUCUUUUUCUUUUUUUUUUUGUUGUUUUCUUCCAGAAUACAUACAAAAAAAUACCCAUUCUCUUCGAUGGUAUACACCUUAAAAAUAAUUGCAAUUUGAAAUCAGAGCUGACAAAUUGUGACUUUUUUUUUCAUUUUUUUUGUAACAAACAUGCAUGUAAAUUUGUGUUUCAAUCAGACAUUAAAUAACGUACAAUACAAUCAUAGCAAUUUUAAAGUAACAUUAAAGAGAAGACCUCUA